CAUUUCCAACUAGCUGGCGGGGGCGGAAGAUGGCGACGCCCCUCGGGUGGUCGAAGGCGGGGUCAGGAUCUGUGUGUCUCGCUUUAGAUCAACUGCGGGACGUGAUUGAGUCUCAGGAGGAACUAAUCCACCAGCUGAGGAACGUGAGGGCGCCCCUUCUACUCCAGCCCCAGGCCCUCCCUCAGCCAGGCUCUGUUGCAGAUGGUUCUCCAGGACGAAAAUUUUGUCAGUAAAGAAGAGUUCCAGGCAGUGGAGAAGAAGCUGGUGGAAGAGAAAGCUGCCCAUGCCAAAACCAAGGUCCUCCUGGCCAAGGAAGAGGAGAAGUUACAGUUUGCCCUCGGAGAGGUAGAGGUGCUAUCCAAGCAGCUGGAGAAAGAGAAGCUGGCCUUUGAAAAAGCGCUCUCCAGUGUCAAGAGCAAAGUCCUUCAGGAGUCCAGCAAGAAGGACCAGCUCAUCACCAAGUGCAAUGAGAUUGAGUCUCACAUUAUAAAGCAAGAAGAUAUACUUAAUGGCAAAGAGAAUGAGAUUAAAGAGUUGCAGCAAGUUAUCAGCCAGCAGAAACAGAUCUUCAGCCCACCACCAGCCGGCUCCGUUGCAGGAAUCACAUGUCUGACUUCCGGAUCCAGAAGCAGCAGGAGAGCUACAUGGCCCAGGUGCUGGACCAGAAGCAUAAGAAAGCCUCAGGGACACGUCAGGCCCGCAGCCACCAGCAUCCCAGGGAAAAAUAAAAUGGCCGCCGCUUUCCUGUUCUCUGGCUGUAAUCCCCAGCCUCUGCCUUCUCUGCUCUGGGAGUCCCCAGCCUCUAGCCCCUGCUACUUCCCUCCCUCUUGGAUAGUGGUAGGGGUCCACAAGGUGGGGGCUUGUAGCCUAGGGGAGGAGCUGGGUCUUUGUUGUCUGGUAGGCACCACCGCUUCCUUUGGGUAUUUAAUCCCUUCCUAUAUAAACAGCCCUGGUUACCCAGUAAUAUUCCACCCCACUCCCAGUGUCCUGGUAAAUUUAACUUCCCAACUUGACUACAGGGCCGGAAGCCCUGACCAGAAACUUCAAAGACAGUGGGUUCCAGAACCACAAGGAAUUUGGGAAGUCAGUUUCCAUCACAUGACAAUAAUGUUAUACCUGCAAAUUGCAUUUGCACCUGCUGACACCUCCCCCAAACGGGAGCUUCACAAUGGGAGGAAGAGAAAAGACAAUGCUGUGUGUGGUUUUAAGGUGGAGAAACAAUCUGGGAAGGGACCUCAAUUUGCACAAGUUGCACAGGCAGGGCUGGAUGGGAUGGAGCAGCAACAUUUUUUCAGAAGCCAUCACCGAGUGCCCCCUAGGUGAUCAUGGGGACACACCCAGGCAGAGGACCCACUUCAGGGGUCAGAUUAGCCCAGUGUAGCCUGUCCUGGGUCGGUUUGAGGCCAAGUGCACAGGAGGGGGCAGUGCUCUUGCUCCAGGGCCAGCUGGGGCCUGAGUCAUAGCAGGACCUUGAAGCCAGAAGUUUAAGGGCAAGUGGUGCCCACAGUUGUAAGACAAUGACAGGUGGUGGUUGCCUCCCCACCAGCGCCUGUCCCCAGGGCAGGUCCUAAGGCUGUGGGGGCUGAAGUUAGGGCCUUGUGAAUACCUGGGGGAGCACAGGGCUGUUCUGGCCGCAGGGGCCUUUGGAGCUGGGACCACAAGCUACUUCGAAGCUUCCUGUAGGACCCCACAUCGGUAUCCAGGGCCUGUUCUAGGUGCUGAGGCAGACUGAAAGCUAGAGCUGUCCACUCCAGCUCCUUCCAAUAGGUCCCACCGAGGGCAGUGGGUCCAGCCAGUGGUAGUACCUUCCUGAGGCCCUGAGGAGUCAGGGAAGCCUCUAGCGGUGCUCCUCACUCUACUGAAGGGGAUCAGGAAGAGUGUAACUGGGGUCAAGAAAGGUGGUGUGUGCACCCUUAAGAGCUCUAGCUGAGGCCAGCAAUGGCAAUGGGGGUCCCCUGCAGUGAUGCUAAGGCACCCGGGGCUGAGGGGAAGAUGAAAUUGCUGGCCCUACCUGAGUCUCCUGGCCUGAAGGUCUGGUUCACCCGCUCACAGCCUGAACUGCACACAGCAGUGCCUGACUUCAGGCGGAUCCCUGCUGGGCUUCAGUUUCCUCACCUGUGAUAGGUGGAGUUGGGCCUAACUCCUGGCUCCAAGGCUUUGAAAGUUGGGCCUGCCAUUCCCUCACCUGCCUGUCAGCCAAAGCUUGGAGCCCACCCCAGGUACUCCGGCUUGUGCCUGAGAAGGGGGUUAGUUGGGCAUGGGGGCUGGACAGGGAAGGGUGCAGGGCCCAGGUCUUUUCUGCUGCCGGCGCCGCUGGCUCAGGAGUGGACGCGGCCGCUUUAAGGCGCGGUGACCCCCACGGCAUCCUCGGGCGGGGCGGGGACAGUGCCGGCGCCACCAGCGGAGGCGAAUGCGAGGGAGAUAGUGCACGGCGUCCGGCCCCACCAUGCUGACCGCGCUCGCCCCGCCAGCCCUGCCUGGGAUCCCGAGGCAGCUGCCCACGGCCCCCGCGCGGCGCCAGGACUCCUCCGGUUCGUCAGGCUCCUACUACACGGCUCCAGGUUCUCCGGAGCCCCCGGACGUUGGGCCGGACGCGAAAGGCCCAGCGAAUUGGCCCUGGGUGGCUCCUGGGCGGGGGGCGGGCGCGCAGCCUCGCCUGUCCGUCAGCGCCCAGAAUAGCCGCCAGCGGCACGGGCCCGGCUCGGGUUUCCCGCGAGGCCCAGGUUCCGGCCCACGGCCACCCCAGCCCCAGCUGCGCACGCUGCCGUCGGGGGAGAUGGAAGUCAUCUUCGGCGUCGGACCCCUGUUCGGCUGCUCCGGCGCAGACGAUCGCGAGGCGCAACAACAGUUCACGGAGCCGGCCUUCAUCAGCCCCUUGCCGCCGGGGCCAGCGUCUCCCGCCGCGGUCCCACGCCAGUCCCAGGUCCCCGAUGGUGGCUCCCGCUGGGCCACCUACCUAGAGCUGCGGCCCCGUGGGCCAAGUCCUGCCGCCCCAGCGCAGUUCGAGUGUGUGGAGGUGGCUCUGGAGGAGGGCGCCGCGCCCGCCAGGCCCCGGACAGUGCCCAAGCGUCAGAUCGAGCUGCGCCCCCGGCCCCAGAGUCCCCCAAGGGCGGCCGGCGCGCCGCGCCCCCGGCUGCUCCUGCGCACCGGUUCCCUGGACGAGUCGCUGGGCCCCCUGCAGGCCGCCGCGGGCUUCGUGCAGACGGCGUUGGCCAGAAAACUGAGCCCCGAGGCCCCGGCCCCGAGCAGCGCCACCUUCGGGUCCACGGGGCGGUCGGAACCUGAGACCCGGGAAACGGCCCGCAGCACCCACGUGGUCCUGGAGAAGGCUAAGUCUCGGCCACUUCGCGUACGAGAUAAUUCGGCCCCCGCCAAGGCCCCGAGGCCGUGGCCCAGCCUCCGCGAGCGCGCGAUUCGGCGCGACAAGCCUGCGCCCGGGACGGAGCCGCUGGGUCCUGUUAGUUCCAGCAUCUUCCUUCAGUCAGAGGAGAAGAUCCAGGAGGCGCGGAAGACUCGGUUCCCGCGAGAGGCGCCGGAUCGAACUGUUCAGAGGGCACGGAGUCCGCCUUUUGAGUGUAGGAUCCCCUCGGAGGUUCCGAGUAGGGCUGUGAGGCCAAGGAGCCCGUCCCCGCCACGGCAGACUCCAAAUGGGGCUGUACGGGGUCCUCGCUGCCCGUCGCCCCAGAACCUGUCCCCGUGGGAUCGGACUACUCGGAGGGUGAGUAGCCCAUUGUUCCCUGAAGCCUCCUCCGAGUGGGAAAAUCAAAAUCCUGCCGUCGAGGAAACUGUCAGCAGGAGAAGCCCUUCCCCUCCGAUCCUUUCCCAGUGGAAUCAGUGUGUUGCUGGGGAAAGGAGCCCGUCCCUCGAAGCCCCUUCCCUGUGGGAGAUUCCACAUUCGGCAGUCGCGGAUGCGGUGGAGCCACGUAGCAGCCCGUCCCCGCCGGCCUUCUUCCCGUGGGAGGCUCCAGAUCGUCCUAUUGGAACUUGGGGCCCAUCUCCCCAAGAGACAUGGGAUCCCAUGGGGCCGGGCUCAUCGAUAGCAUUUACUCAGGAAGCUCAGAAUGGGUUAACUCAGGAGGAGUUGGCACCGCCUACACCGUCCGCACCCGGCACUCCAGAACCAACAGAGAUGCAGAGUCCAUCCACGCGGGAAAUUUCAGAUCUUGCCUUUGGAGGGAGUCAGCAGUCCCCAGAGGUAGCAGCACCCGAGCCGCCCGGCAGCCACCCUGUGGGCACCCUGGACGCGGAUAAGUGCCCGGAAGUCUUGGGUCCUGGAGAGGCGGCCUCGGGACGCCCGCGCAUGGCCAUUCCGCGGCCUCGAGACGUGCGCAAGUUGGUGAAGACCACGUACGCGCCAGGCUUCCCGGCAGGAGCACAAGGCUCUGGGCUGCCUGCGCCUCCUGCCGACCCCUGCGGGGAGGAGGGCGGCGAAUCCAAGACGCAAGAGCCGCCAGCACUGGGGCCCCCCGCCCCGGCUCACUACACUUCCGUUUUCAUCAAGGAUUUUCUACCGGUGGUGCCGCACCCCUACGAGCCUCCUGAACCGUCCUUCGACACGGUCGCCCGGGACGCCUCACAGCCCAACGGGGUCCUGCGGCGGAGGGCAGAGAACAGCACGGCGAAGCCCUUCAAGCGCACAGAGAUCCGCCUGCCUGGGGCCCUGGCCUUGGGUCGCCGGCCCGAGGUAACCUCGCGAGUGCGAGCGCGCGGCCCUGGAGGAGAGAACAGGGAUGUAGAGGCCCAGCGCCUGGUCCCCGACGGCGACGGUCGGACCAGCCCUCUAGGCGGCGCCCGCAGCUCAUCCCAGCGCUCCCCCGUAGGGCCAGCAGGGGUCCGAUCGCCCCGCCCCGGCUCCCCUCAGAUGCAAGCCAGCCCGAGCCCUGGGAUAGCACCCAAACCGAAGACACCACCUACGGCCCCCGAGCCCGCGGCUGCCGUCCAGGCGCCACUCCCGCGGGAGCCCCUGGCGUUGGCGGGCAGGACGGCCCCAGCCCAGCCCCGCGCUGCCUCGGCGCCUCCCACGGACCG